CUUCUCGGCCGAGCGGGGCCGCGGGCGGAUGGAGGUCUGGGGGGGGUCGGCCGGGAACGCCGGCGCCGGGAGCCUCCGAGGCCGACGGCUCUUCUGGGGCCGCCCCUGCCCCCGCGGAGUGAUUCAGCCCCGGCUCGCUGCCUCUGCCCGGCGGGUCGGUGCAUCCCCGAACCGAGGCCCGGGGCGUUCCGCUCCAGCAGACCGAAGCCAGAAACGCCGCCCCCGCCACCCAGGCCGAGUGUGUCGAGAAGGGGCCGGCGCCCUUUUCAGGGUGUCAGGGGACUGUGUGCCCGCUGUCCUGACGAAGCACAGGGUGGAGCGAGCGCUGGUGUGCUGGGUGGAUUCUCAUCCCCCGAUAGCUGGAAAGUUGCCCCUCAUGACACUGGCCACUGCAUCGACGGCCUCUGUUGCUGGGUGUUUCUUCUAAGCACGGGCUGACGCACGAGGCACACAGGAAGGAGGUGGAGCAGGUGUAUCUGCGCUGUGCGGCGGGUGCCGUGGAGUGGAUGUACCCAACAGGUGCUCUCAUCGUUAACCUGCGGCCCAACACCUUCUCGCCUGCCCGGCACCUGACCGUGUGCAUCAGGUCCUUCACGGACUCCUCGGGGGCCAAUAUUUAUUUGGAAAAAACUGGAGAACUGAGACUGCUGGUACCAGACGGGGACGGCAGGCCCGGCCGGGUGCAGUGUUUUGGCCUGGAGCAGGGCGGCCUGUUCGUGGAGGCCACGCCGCAGCAGGAUAUCGGCCGGAGGACCACAGGCUUCCAGUACGAGCUGGUUAGGAGGCACAGGGCGUCGGACCUGCACGAGCUGUCUGCGCCGUGCCGUCCCUGCAGUGACACCGAGGUGCUCCUAGCCGUCUGCACCAGCGACUUCGCCGUUCGAGGCUCCAUCCAGCAAGUUACCCACGAGCCUGAGCGGCAGGACUCAGCCAUCCACCUGCGCGUGAGCAGACUCUAUCGGCAGAAAAGCAGGGUCUUCGAGCCGGUGCCCGAGGGUGACGGCCACUGGCAGGGGCGCGUCAGGACGCUGCUGGAGUGUGGCGUGCGGCCGGGGCAUGGCGACUUCCUCUUCACUGGCCACAUGCACUUCGGGGAGGCGCGGCUCGGCUGUGCCCCACGCUUCAAGGACUUCCAGAGGAUGUACAGGGAUGCCCAGGAGAGGGGGCUGAACCCUUGUGAGGUUGGCACGGACUGACUCCGUGGGCCGCUGCCCUUCCUCUCCUGAUGAGUCACAGGCUGCGGUGGGCGCUGCGGUCCUGGUGGGGCCGUGCGGUGAGGGCCGCGCGCUGGGAGCCGCAUGCCCUGGGCCCAGGCCUGACCCUGGUACCGAAGCUGUGGACGUUCUCGCCACACUCAACCCCAUGAGCUUCCAGCCAAGGAUGCCCUGGCCGAUUGGAAAUGCUGUAAAAUGCAAACUAAGUUAUUAUAUUUUUUUUUGGUAAAAAAGAAAUGUCCAUAGGAAACAAAUUCCCGUGUCUUAAAACGCCUUGGUGUGCCGUCUGAUACUGUUCUCUAAAGACGUUAGGAGUCACGGCAUCUGGCCUGCGGUUGGGUGAAGCACUGGCCGUUGGGCACAGUGGAUGUGUGAAAAGGUGCCAUUCAGAGUUGUUAUUCUCAUGACGGAAGUUUUGGAGCCAAAUAAUACGUUUUUUAUUUUCAUUUUAUUUUUAAAGGAUGAGCUUUGGUCCUUUUCAGGCCGCCGGUUGUUUCCGUUCCCGAGAAUAAAGACGAGGAUCCGACCA